AGCUUUGACAGAGCGCAAUGGCGGCAACCGCGUCUGCAGGGGUGCCGGCGACCGUGUCAGAAAAGCAAGAGUUUUACCAGCUUCUGAAGAACCUGAUCAAUCCAAGCUGUAUGGUGCGGAGGCAAGCAGAGGAAAUCUAUGAAAAUAUCCCAGGUCUGUGUAAGACUACCUUCCUCUUAGAUGCCGUCAGAAAUAGAAGAGCAGGUUAUGAGGUGAGACAAAUGGCUGCCGCACUGCUACGACGGCUUUUGUCCUCUGGGUUUGAGGAGGUUUAUCCAAAUCUGCCUGCUGAUGUUCAGAGAGAUGUCAAGAUUGAACUGAUUCUGGCUGUUAAGUUAGAAACACAUGCUAGCAUGAGGAAAAAACUUUGUGAUAUUUUUGCAGUGCUGGCCAGGAAUUUGAUAGAUGAGGAUGGCACUAACCACUGGCCGGAAGGUCUGAAGUUUCUUAUUGAUUCAAUCUACUCCAAAAAUGUGGUUCUAUGGGAAGUUGCACUUCACGUUUUCUGGCACUUUCCUGGGAUUUUUGGGACCCAAGAGCGGCAUGAUUUGGAUAUCAUCAAACGGUUGUUGGACCAGUGUAUUCAAGAUCAAGAACAUCCAGCAAUCAGGACAUUAUCCGCUAGAGCUGCAGCUGCAUUUGUACUUGCUAAUGAGAAUAAUAUUGCUCUUUUCAAAGACUUUGCAGACUUGCUUCCUGGAAUCUUACAGGCUGUGAAUGACUCAUGCUACCAGGAUGAUGAUUCAGUGCUAGAAUCCCUUGUUGAGAUUGCAGAUACCGUACCUAAGUACUUGGGUCCUUAUUUAGAAGAUACUCUACAGUUGAGUUUGAAGUUAUGUGGAGACUCUAGGCUUAGUAAUCUGCAGCGCCAGCUGGCCCUCGAAGUUAUAGUGACCUUGUCUGAAACUGCCACUCCGAUGUUGAAAAAACAUACAAAUAUUAUUGCACAGGCAGUUCCUCAUAUAUUAGCAAUGAUGGUUGAUCUACAAGAUGAUGAGGACUGGGUAAAUGCUGAUGAAAUGGAAGAAGAUGAUUUUGACAGCAAUGCAGUUGCUGCGGAGAGUGCACUAGACAGACUGGCUUGUGGGCUUGGUGGAAAAGUUGUUUUACCAAUGACCAAGGAGCAUAUCAUGCAGAUGCUUCAGAGCCCUGACUGGAAGUAUCGACAUGCUGGAUUAAUGGCCUUAUCUGCCAUUGGAGAAGGAUGCCAUCAACAAAUGGAAUCAAUUCUAGAUGAAACAGUUAACUCCGUUUUGCUUUUUCUUCAGGAUCCUCAUCCAAGGGUGAGGGCUGCAGCCUGUACUACACUUGGACAGAUGGCUACAGAUUUUGCACCUAAUUUCCAAAAGAAAUUUCAUGAAACAGUGAUUGCAGCUCUGUUACGUACCAUGGAAAAUCAAGGUAAUCAGCGUGUGCAAUCACAUGCAGCUUCUGCUCUUAUUAUUUUUAUUGAAGACUGCCCUAAAUCAUUGCUAGUUCUAUAUGUGGAUAGUAUGGUGAAAAAUCUACAUUCCGUCUUGGUGAUUAAACUUCAAGAGUUGAUUCGGAAUGGAACUAAGUUGGCUUUGGAACAACUUGUGACAACCAUUGCAUCAGUUGCAGAUACAAUAGAAGAAAAAUUUGUCCCAUAUUAUGAUAUAUUCAUGCCCUCACUAAAGCACAUUGUUGAGCUUGCUGUUCAGAAGGAACUCAAGCUUCUGAGAGGAAAAACUAUCGAGUGCAUUAGCCAUAUUGGUCUUGCUGUUGGGAAGGAAAAAUUUAUGCAAGAUGCAUCAAAUGUGAUGCAGCUGUUGUUGAAGACACAAUCAGACUUAAAUAAUAUGGAAGAUGAUGACCCUCAGACCUCUUACAUGGUUUCAGCAUGGGCUAGAAUGUGUAAAAUUCUUGGAAAAGAUUUUCAACAGUACCUUCCACUGGUUAUCGAGCCUCUUAUUAAGACUGCUUCAGCUAAACCUGAUGUUGCUCUCUUAGACACACAGGAUGUGGAAAAUAUGAGUGACGAUGAUGGCUGGCAAUUUGUAAAUCUUGGAGACCAGCAGAGUUUUGGAAUUAAAACUUCAGGACUUGAAGCAAAAGCAACUGCUUGCCAAAUGUUGGUUUACUAUGCUAAGGAGUUAAGGGAAGGGUUUGUGGAAUAUACAGAACAAGUUGUGAAGCUGAUGGUUCCUUUACUGAAAUUUUAUUUCCAUGACAAUGUUCGAGUGGCAGCAGCAGAGUCCAUGCCUUUUCUCCUGGAAUGUGCAAGAAUUCGUGGCCCAGAGUAUCUUGCACAGAUGUGGCAAUUCAUAUGUGACCCCUUAAUCAAGGCUAUUGGUACUGAACCAGAUACAGAUGUGCUCUCAGAAAUAAUGAAUUCUUUUGCAAAGUCCAUUGAAGUUAUGGGAGAUGGUUGCCUUAAUGAUGAACACUUGGAAGAACUGGGAGGAAUACUGAAAGCAAAACUUGAAGGGCACUUUAAAAACCAAGAAUUGAGACAGGUGAAAAGACAGGAAGAAAACUAUGAUCAACAGGUUGAGAUGUCUCUGCAAGAUGAGGAUGAAUGUGAUGUUUAUAUUCUGACCAAAGUAUCAGAUAUUUUGCACUCAUUAUUUAGUACUUAUAAGGAAAAGAUUUUACCAUGGUUUGAACAACUACUUCCAUUAAUUGUAAAUCUAAUUUGUUCAAGUAGGCCAUGGCCAGACAGACAGUGGGGAUUGUGCAUAUUUGAUGACAUCAUAGAGCACUGCAGUCCAACUUCAUUUAAAUAUGUAGAAUAUUUUCGGUGGCCAAUGCUACUAAAUAUGCGAGAUAACAACCCUGAAGUCAGGCAAGCUGCUGCUUAUGGCCUGGGUGUCAUGGCACAGUUUGGUGGAGAUGAUUAUCGUUCUUUAUGUUCAGAAGCUGUUCCACUUCUGGUAAAAGUUAUUAAGUGUGCAAAUUCCAAAACCAAAAAAAAUGUCAUUGCUACAGAGAACUGUAUCUCAGCAAUAGGGAAGAUUUUGAAGUUUAAGCCUAACUGUGUAAAUGUAGAUGAAGUUCUUCCACACUGGUUAUCAUGGCUUCCACUGCAUGAAGAUAAAGAGGAAGCUAUUCAGACUUUGAGUUUUCUCUGUGACCUAAUUGAAAGUAACCACCCAGUUGUAAUUGGUCCAAAUAAUUCCAAUCUUCCCAAAAUAAUCAGUAUAAUUGCAGAAGGAAAAAUUAAUGAGACUAUUAACUAUGAGGAUCCUUGUGCCAAACGCCUAGCUAAUGUCGUGCGUCAGGUACAGACUUCUGAAGAUUUAUGGUUGGAAUGUGUAUCACAACUUGAUGAUGAACAGCAGGAAGCCUUACAGGAGUUGCUAAAUUUUGCUUGAAGCACUUUAAUAUAACUUGAAUAUUAUCUAUUAUAAAAGUAACUACAAAUAAGUGUUGUGAAUAGAUUUUAUUAUAAAUCAGAGAACUGUUUUCUCCCUGCUAAGCAGUUUAUAGUUCUUCUCCAUGUUUCUCCAGAAUUAAUCAGUGUUAGUCCUCUGUUUAUCUCGCAUGUUUUAUCUUCCAAACACAGACCUUGGUGAUAACCUGUGCUUCAAACUGUCUUAAACAAUGUUUGUCACCUUUCCCCUAGUUGAUGUAAAGUAUAUAAAUUGUUGCUAUUUGUUUGAACUAUUAUUGAUGCUAGCCAAGCAGUAUACUUGAUGUGAAGAUGUCAUGCUAUCACAAUAUGCUAAGAGCUCACAAAAAUAAGAUAGAAUUUCCAGGACAAACAUCUUUGGAAUUGUGAGUGAAGGAUAUAGUGGCAGGCUUGUCCCUCUUUAAUUAAUACUCUUGGUAUUUGUGGUGAUGGGAGGAUGCUGUUACUAGGAGAGUUUUGAGAUACUGCAGUGGAUGUGGGAUGUAUAUGAACUUCUUCAUAAUGUACUCCUGGGAACUGGGUAGGACAUAUCCAUAUUGUAGUUCCCAAGGUGUCUGGUUGAGAGUUAGAGAACUUUUAAAUUUCUUUAGCCAGACAGGUCUCUAUUUUUUUAAGUUAUCCAGGACUCCAAGAACCAUAGUUACUGAAAAGGGAGUCCUGAUACAUCUAAUAUUGGUAGCAUGUAACAGUGUUUGACAAAGAGUAAGUAAGCAGUAUUCUUGGGAGUCAGUGUUAUGUGUUUCAGCAGAGUAUUAUUUUGUAUAUGUAUGCCAUUUUCUCCCUGCAAAGCAGCUCAACAAGAGAAAAAGCUCUAGUUAUAGGGCUUAAAUUGAUUUCUAUUUCAAAUAAUUUCCUAAGAGAUUCUAGAGUAGAACUGAAGAGUAUUCUAUUGGAAAAGUGAAAGGAAAGAAAUGUAAUUUUCUUUGAACAUGAAAAAGAAAACAACUUUGAGAGUAGUCAUUUAGCAGUAGAUGUGCAUUAUUAUGAGAAAACAGUUCUAUAAGUCCAGGGUUAAUUAUAUUAAUUGGAAUGUCAGUCUUUAAUGUCGAGCUUAUUGUAGGGUAGAAAAGAGCUUUCUACUCAGCUAACGAUUACUCAUUGAUCCAAAACUUAAAUACAUCUAUAAUUUCCUGGGGCUAUUGUGAGUACUGUGUAUGUAUUUAGCAAAUAUUUAAGACCUAGUAAGUGCUCAAUAAAUUGUAGCUGUUAUUGCUGUUGUUGUUUGUA